ACGCGGGGCCCAAGAUGGCGGCCAGCCGGUACCGGCGUUUUCUUAAGCUCUGUGAGGAAUGGCCAGUGGACGAGACCAAACGGGGCCGGGACUUGGGCGCUUACCUGCGACAGCGGGUAGCACAGGCCUUUCGGGAGGGAGAGAAUACCCAGGUUGCAGAGCCUGAGGCCUGUGAUCAGAUGUACGAGAGCUUAGCGCGACUCCAUUCAAACUACUACAAACACAAGUACCCUCGCCCCAGAGACACCAGCUUCAGUGGCCUGUCGUUGGAAGAGUACAAGCUGAUCCUGUCCACAGACACCUUGGAAGAGCUUAAGGAAAUAGAUAAAGGCAUGUGGAAGAAACUGCAGGAGAAGUUUGCCCCCAAGGGUCCUGAGGAGGAUCAUAAGGCCUGAGCUCAGGCCUUACCUCGUGCACAUACCUAGGUGUGGAGUCUUGUACAUUGCCAUCGUCAAUAAAACUGCCCCAGUUUCCCCUUGACCUUACGGUUUGGGAAUCUCCUCUAGCUUUCCCAGAAAGGAAGCCCUUGCUGCUCUAAAGAAAGUUUCAGCCUGAGAAGGGAUGGUGAUUGAGCUAUCUGCUGUGACUGCUGCUCAGGGUAGGGAAAUCUCCUGGGGAGAGGAAAUGCAGGUUUCCCUCUGGGCCUGAUGAGGGUAAUGGGGCCUCGGCACAAGGUGCUUCCUGCAUUGCCACGGGAGCCCCCGCCCCUCUGGCACGGGUCUGGUGUCUCCUGGCAAGAUACUCAGGCUCCCUUUUGUUGUAGGAGCUCCUGGGAGGAAGCCAAAAAUAGCAGUAAAUACUGAAAAGGGCAUCCUGUUGCAAACAGAAAGCAGUAGGGAGGUGUGAGGCCGAGAGAGGCAAAAAGCCUGCUUGGCCCUCAUCCCCACUGACUCAGAGAAGGAUGGACCUUAGGCCUCUAUCCCUGACCUUGCAAAAACCCACAUUGCCCAGUUGGCUUAAGGGACAGGGAAGCUAUAGACAGGCCUUGGCCAAGCGGGGCCUCAGCUGCAGUUGGCUUCAGCACUGUGGGCAGGUUCUGUAGGUGGCCACAAGUCAGAGGCCCUGCUGGCUGAGGACACACACAGGGUCACCUCAUUAUUCCAUGGAACCUUGGCUCUUACUGAUAUUGAGCAUCCUUCUCUCUGGAACCGUGAGGGACAGGGCUGGGCCCACAGCGGCCCUGGUGGGUACAAAGUGGAAGUGGGUUCUUAACCUCGUCUGUGUCUAGACUCCUCAGGAUGUUCUGAAAUGCAUAAAAUAAAAUCGACAGGACUGCCGUAGAAA